AGAGCCCAGAUCGGAAGAGCCGAGUCCGGGCAGAGGGGUCCGCGGGCUCUGGAGGUGCUGGACGGGUGCGAUCCGAGAGCAGACCGGGGCCCUCGCGAGCCUCUCCCGGCCCCUGCCCGCGAUGAGCGAGGCCAGCCGACUGUGCUCCGGCUACUACAGCCUCAACCAGAGCUUCGUGGAGCCCUUCCAGUGCCCCCGGCGCGGCGAGGGGGCAGCGCUCCAGUAUUGCUGCGGCUUCGCCGACCUCAAGUACUGCUGCAGCGAGCCGGGCAGCUACUUCCCCUACAAGCACAGCUACAUGUGGAGCCUCAGCAUUGGUGCCUUGAUUGGACUAGGAAUUGCUGCCCUUGUUUUACUCGCCUUUGUCAUCAGUGUCUGUGUCCUUUGCUAUUUAUUUCUGUAUACGAAACCUCAAAGAUUAGACACUGGCCUUAAGCUUCAACACUUAGAGGCUUCUUCCACUCAAGAAGGCAAGUCAAAUGGAAAAACCAAAGCCCUCAAUUCAAAUGCAGCAUCAAAUGCAACAAAUGAAACAUACUAUGAAGCUGAUGAUAUAAUUCAAGAAAAAACAAUGGAUGCAACACAAAUCCACAUUGCUUAUUAACUAAAAAUUCUGUGUUUUAAAUGCUUACUGGAGAGAUGGGACAAUAAAAAUAAAGCGUGCACUUGAAACGGUUUGUAAUAUUGCUUUUCAAAAAUUCGUCACUCACAAAGCAAGACACAGCUGCAUUUUUGAUCAUUCAGUUACUUUAUUAAACGCACAUUAAGGUUU